AUGAGGAGAGAUGAGGCGCGGGCACACUCUCCAGGCCCGGCACCCGCGGGAACGGGGGACACGCGGGACUUCGGCAGUCCCAGUAACUUGCUUUGCUGUUCUGAGACCUCAGCGGGGCGGUCAGACCUCUGCUGUCUCCGCAGCGAGUUGCAGUACUUGGCGCGGGGAGAGGAACUCGAGAGGAAGCUCACUGCGCCUCGCCCCUGGCGUCGGCAGCGGCUGUCUGGGACCCUGUGGUCCGGAUUCACCAAGUGGCGCAGAGCUGGAAUCGAGUGGGUGCACAGUUUCCAGGCUCCGACUAUUACUGGCCUCGAAGAUCGUGACGCCGCCAGUAGGUGUCAGUCAUUUGCCGCACAGCCACCUUUGAGAUCCACCUGUGUCUCCCAGCGGCCGAAUCCAGGUUUCCUUCCUAUUCGCACUUGGAGAACUCAUGCAGAUUGCCGUCAGGAGUGGCCUCAGAGAUCCGGAGUGGGCGAAUGGGAAAUCGCAUCUUACGGCCCAGAACCUGAGCCCUCCACAAGCACUUGGCUCAGUCCCUUGCUCAGGCCACCUCCUGUUCUCUUCUGCUCUGUGAAAGACACUGUUAAGAGAAUGAAAAGACACGCCACAGACUGGAGAAAAUAUUUGCAUAAUACGUAUGUAUCUGCUGAAGCACUGGUAUACAAAAUAUACAUAGAAUGUUAAAACUCAUAAUAAGGUAAAAAAUUAAUGGGCAAAAUAUUUAAACAGAAACCCCGCCAAAGAAGAUAUGCAGAUGGUAAACAGUAUAAAAAGAUGCCAAACAUCAUUGACAUAUGCUAUAUGUCAAUAUUUAGCUAUAUAUAACUAAACAUCAGUAAAUACUUCUGAUUGCAAUUUAAACAUCAGUAAGAUACCAUAAUUGCAAAUUAAACAUCAGUAAGAUAUUACUACACACCAUUCAAUUGGCUAAAAUUCAAAACACCACAUGCUAAGGAGGAGGUGGAGUAACAGGUACUCUCAUUCAUUACUGAUGAGAAUGCAAAAUGGUACAGCCACUUUGGAGGACAGUAUGGCAAUUUCUUACAAAGCUAAAACACAGUCCUACAAUACAAUUCAACCACCACAAUCCACGUGUUUAUCCAAAUGAGCUUAAAGUGAAUGUCCACAUAAGGACCUGCAUGUGAAUGUUUAUAGAAGUUUUAUUCAUAGUUGCCAAAAAUUGGAAGCAACCAAGAAGUCCUUCAACA